AGCCUCGCUGUGGCCUGCGGCUCCCGGGCUGGUAGCGCGCCGCUCUCGGUCGCGCGGAGUGAUCGUGUGGAAUCGCGGGUCGCGGACGCUCGCCGCCGGCCAUAGCUCAGCCUAGCGCCGCCAAGGCCGACGGCCCUCAGCCUCUGCCAUGGACUUCGAGGACGAUUACACACACUCCGCCUGCAGGAAUACUUAUCAGGGCUUUAAUGGAAUGGAUCGUGAUUAUGGCCCUGGAUCUUAUGGAGGGAUGGAUCGUGACUAUGGCCAUGGAUCCUAUGGGGGUCAGAGAUCCAUGGAUUCCUACCUAAACCAGUCAUAUGGCAUGGACAAUCACAGUGGUGGUGGUGGGGGUAGCAGGUUUGGACCUUAUGAGUCUUACGACUCCAGGUCUUCUCUGGGUGGGCGAGAUCUGUACAGAUCUGGCUAUGGUUUUAAUGAACCCGAACAAAGCCGCUUCGGAGGUAGUUAUGGUGGUCGAUUUGAGAGCUCCUACCGGAAUAGCCUUGACUCUUUCGGAGGUAGAAACCAGGGCGGGUCUAGCUGGGAAGCACCUUACUCCCGUUCAAAAUUGAGGCCUGGGUUUAUGGAGGACAGAGGAAGAGAGAAUUACUCUUCCUACAGCAGUUUUUCUUCACCCCAUAUGAAGCCUGCACCUGUAGGCUCUCGGGGGAGAGGAACGCCUGCUUAUCCUGAAAGUACGUUUGGAAGCAGAAACUAUGAUGCUUUUGGAGGACCAUCAACAGGCAGAGGCCGAGGCCGAGGACAUAUGGGUGAUUUUGGAAGCAUUCAUAGACCCGGAAUUGUUGUUGACUAUCAAAACAAAUCCACCAAUGUGACAGUUGCUGCUGCAAGAGGAAUAAAGAGAAAAAUGAUGCAGCCAUUUAAUAAGCCCAGUGGAACCUUUAUCAAGAAACCCAAACUAGCAAAACCUAUGGAGAAGAUAAGCCUCAGCAAAUCACCCACAAAAACUGAUCCUAAAAAUGAAGAGGAAGAAAAGCGGCGAAUUGAGGCUCGGCGAGAGAAACAAAGGCGCAGAAGAGAAAAAAACAGUGAGAAAUACGGAGAUGGAUACAGAAUGGCAUUUACAUGUUCAUUUUGUAAAUUUCGAACAUUUGAAGAAAAAGAUAUUGAACUGCAUCUGGAAAGUUCUUCACAUCAGGAAACAUUAGAUCAUAUACAGAAACAAACUAAAUUUGAUAAAGUAGUUAUGGAGUUUUUGCAUGAGUGUAUGGUGAAUAAAUUCAAGAAAACAUCUAUUCGUAAGCAACAGACAAAUAAUCAAACAGAAGUAGUUAAAAUAAUUGAAAAAGAUGUUAUGGAAGGUGUUACUGUAGAUGAUCACAUGAUGAAGGUAGAGACAGUUCAUUGCAGCGCUUGCAGUGUUUAUAUCCCUGCUUUACAUAGUUCAGUUCAGCAGCACUUAAAAUCUCCUGAUCAUAUCAAAGGGAAGCAGGCUUAUAAGGAACAAAUAAAAAGAGAGAGUGUCUUGACUGCUACAAGCAUUUUAAAUAAUCCAAUAGUGAAGGCGCGAUAUGAACGUUUUGUUAAGGGUGAGAAUCCUUUUGAAAUUCAAGACCAUUCUCAGGAUCAGCAAAUAGAAGGAGAUGAGGAGGAUGAAGAGAAGAUUGAUGAACCUAUUGAAGAAGAGGAGGAUGAAGAUGAGGAAGAAGAAGCAGAGGAAGUGGGGGAAGUAGAGGAAGUGGAAGAAGUAGAGGAAGUGAGAGAAGGAGGAAUAGAGGGCGAGGGAAAUAUACAGGGAGUAGGGGAAGGAGGGGAAGUAGGGGUAGUGGGAGAAGUAGAGGGAGUGGGGGAAGUAGAGGAAGUAGAGGAAUUAGAGGAAGAGACAGCAAAGGAAGAACCUGCUGACUUCCCUGUUGAGCAACCUGAAGAAAAUUAAAUAUAAGGUAUUAGAUUUAAAAGGAGCUUUACAUUUCGGUUCUAAUGUAAAAAAGGGUAAGAAAUUUAAUAGCUUAAAAUAUGAAUUAACACCCAUGUUGCAUGCAUUCCACAUAUUAAAAUUUGUUUUAUAUAAUUUCUAAAUGUUUAACAUUUGUUUAAUAAAAUGAAGGCAAAACUAUUUUAGUUUAGUUUUUAUAGCUACCAGACUUAGAUCCGAUAAAUUGUUUGUAUAAUUUUUAAGCUUAAUUUUUAUUACUUUAUUGGUGUUAAGGAUAACAAAUGUGUAUUGUUAGUAUAUCUAUUCUAAUCAUUUUAUCUUAAAUGCUGCUCUUGGGAGUGAAUAUUCAAGUGUGCAUCAAUUUUUUGAAUACUUACCCUGGAAGAUAUAAACUGGGCAAGUAUUUUGUGCUCUGUGUAUUUUUUUACUGCAUUAGACAUUGAAUAGUAAUUUGCGUUAAGAUACGCUUAAAGGCUCUUUGUGACCAUGUUUCCCUUUGUAGCAAUAAAAUGUUUUUUACGAAAACUUUCUCCCUGGAUUAGCAGUUUAAAUGAAACAGAGUUCAUCAAUGAAAUGAGUAUUUAAAAUAAAAAUUUGCCUUAAUGUAUCAGUUCAGCUCACAAGUAUUUUAAGAUGAUUGAGAAGACUUGAAUUAAAGAAAAAAAAAUUCUCAAUCAUAUUUUUAAAAUAUAAGACUAAAAUUGUUUUUAAAACACAUUUCAAAUAGAAGUGAGUUUGAACUGACCUUAUUUAUACUCUUUUUAAGUUUGUUCCUUUUCCCUGUGCCUGUGUCAAAUCUUCAAGUCUUGCUGAAAAUACAUUUGAUACAAAGUUUUCUGUAGUUGUGUUAGUUCUUUUGUCAUGUCUGUUUUUGGCUGAAGAACCAAGAAGCAGACUUUUCUUUUAAAAGAAUUAUUUCUCUUUCAAAUAUUUCUAUCCUUUUUAAAAAAUUCCUUUUUAUGGCUUAUAUACCUACAUAUUUAAAAAGAGAACAUGAGCUUGAUAGAGGAUCUAUUCUUAAAUAAUUUAUUUUCAAACAACCGUCUAUGUCACUAAAAAGUAGUGCUCUUAUUUUUUUCAAUCUUUACUGUGGCCUCUUUUGAGAGUAGGGUCCGUAGUUUUUUUUUUUUUUCUUUUUUGGGACAGGGUUUCACUCUGUCACCCAGGCUGGAGUGCAGUGUAGCCUCAACCUCCUGGGCUCAAGCGAUCCUCCAACUUAGCCUCCCAAGUAGCUGGGACUGUUAAGUGUGAGCCACCAUGCCCAGCUAAUUUUUGUAGUUUUUGUAGAGACAGGGUUUUACCAUGUUGUCCAGGCUGGUUUUGAACUCCUGGGCUCAAGUGACCUGUCUGUCUUGGCCUCCCACAGUGCUGGGAUUGCAGGUGUGAGCCACCAUGCCUGGCAUAGGGGGCUGUAUUUCAGUGAAAUUAGAAAAGUUUUGAGGCAUCGAAUGGAUAAAUGGAUGGAUAUAUCAAAUUGUAAGGUAUUAAGUGGGUGAAUGUAUGGACAUUUGUAGAAUCCCACAGAUAAUUUAUCUUUUUGUGUAAAAUAAGGCUUUUAAAACUAGACUUUCUGAACCAAUACAGUUUUUUUUUUUUGAGGUGAACUAGGUUUGCCUAGCUUUAAGCUAGCAAUAUCUGAUAGAUACUUGCAUCUAAUUUUAGGGAUUUGGUGCCAAAUAAGAGAAGGGUAGUUGAAGACUAGAUAAAUUUGGAUACUAUCUAGGAGUCUGUAUUUACUUAGCAGGCUUUUGAAAGCCGUUUUGCUUAGGAGUUCAAAUUUUAAGGAUAAUAGGACUUGUUACCCUCUUAUUUCUCCUUUAUUUUUAAAAAUAUUUGUGGAAGGGCUAAGGUAAAAGAAUAAUAAAUUCCUCUAGGUUAUUAGUAUUUGGUUCUUCUGAUACUAAGCUGAGUGAUUUUUUUUAAAACAAUGUCUCUGGUAGUCUGAUUGAGAUAUGAAACUUUUGGGAAGAAAACCAUUAUGUAACAAGAAUCCUAUGUAACAACUGGGUAAAUGUUUUAGAAUGAGAGAUAGGAAAGAACAUCUAAAUAGUACUUUUUUGUGGGACGCAUGAGCCUUUAUACAGCCUAGCUAAUUUGCAAGGUAAUGAUAAAUAAAAGUGUAUUUUGUUACUGUGCUUAAUUCAGAAAUUCAAAUUCAUGUAUUUCCUAUUGGAUAAUUUGUAGGCGGGCAGUUUACUUUAUAGUCAGGUUAGUUUUUGUGAUCCUUAGUGUUUAUAUUUGCAUUGCUUUUGUAAUAAGGAUGUAUAUAAGAUCUUAAACGCCUUUCAACUUCUGUUUUCAAGUAUCACUUGUUUUCUCUAUUACAAAGUGAGAUACAUAGUUCUAAAUAACCAAAGAAAUUUAUUUAUAACCUACACAGUUGUUUCAGCUCCAUGCCUAGGGACUAUCCUGUAUUAUUCGCUUUUUAUCACUUUCUACCUACAGUCUACCAAAAAGUCUGUCUGUUCUACUUCCAAAAUUUAUCUGCCGACUCUUCUACCUCCACUGCAACCAACCCAGUUCAAGUCAUGAUAAUUUCUUGUUAACUAAUCUUGAUUCCACCCUUACCAUGAUAGAUUCAGUUUUCUACACAAGUAUAAGCUUUUAAAAAUGUAAUUCAGAUGAUGUUAAUCUCAUGCUUUUUUUUUUUUUGUACCUAUACAGUUAGAACUCCUUAUCAUGUUGAUCAGACUGGCCUAGCUUUACAACUUUAUAUCAUAUACCAUUCUUACCAGCCAUAAUGGCCUUUUGUUACUUUUUUGAUGAGUUCUUUCCUACAAAGACCUUUGCAUUUUCUUAUUCUAUAGCCUAUACCCAUCAGCUUUCCUUGGCUGAUUCUUCAUCCUUCAGGUCACCUUAAAUGUUAGAAAAGGGGAGUAGUUCUAAAAUGUUUGUAGAAACGAGGAUUUGGGGGUACCAACCUAGAUUUUACUAGAGCAUAUUCUUUGGAGGUGUUCUUUUUUUCUACUUUUUUUUUUUUUUUCUUUAGGUUCUGUCUUUGUCAUGCAGGCUGGAAUUCAGUGGCACGAUCAUGGCUUACUGCAGCUUUGACCUCCUGGGCUCAAGCGGUCGUCCCGCCUUAGCCUCCCAAGUAGCUGGGACCACAGACGUGCACCAUCACACUCAGCUAAUAUUUUUUUUGUAGAGAUGGGGUCUUGCUUUGUUGCCCAGGCUAGUCUUGAACUCCUGGACACAAGCAGUCCUCCCACCUCAGCUUCCCAAAGUGCUAGAAUUACAGGCAUGAGCCACCACGCCUAUCCUGGAGGUGAUAUAUUUUUAACAAAUAUCUCACAUGAUUUUGAAGGUAGUGGUCAGUGAUUGCACUUUGAGGACAUUCAUAGGGCCCUCAUACAAAUUUCUGGUGCCUGUAACUCUUCCCCUAUCAAGGCAGGAGUUUCCGCCCUUUUGAAUAUAAACAUAGGUUUGGGGGAUUCUUCAUAAUACUUUCUGAAAGCACUGGAAUCUAUAACAGACCUGUGGGAGUCAGAAAAUGGGGACUUUUCCCCCCUCAUUUAAUACUUACAACUAUAUUGGUAAGUUAGUAGGAGUAGUAAUUUUCCCAUAUAAUAAGCCCACUCUUGUACAUGUAGAAACAGAGAAAAGAACUACAAAGGUAAAUGUUAGUGCAUGUUGAAAUGUAUUUAAGAACUCUGUUUUUGUUGGCAAGAUUGUUCUUAUUGUAGAAGUGGAUAUUAUCAGAUUAUUUUAGAUGUUAUUCAACAUUUGAUUUAUUUACCAAAUUGUCCUUACUUUGAAUAUAAGCAAACUUUUUUAUUGUGGUAAAGUAUACAUAGCAUAAAAUUACCAUUCUAAUCAUUUUUUAAUGUACCAUUUAGUGGCAUUAAUUACAAGCAACCUUUUUUUUUUUUUUUUGAGACAUAGCCUCACUCUGUCACCCAGGCUGGAGUUCAGUGGCACUAUCUCAGCUCACUGCAAUCUCUGCUUCCUGGGUUCAAGCGAUUCUUGUGCCUCAGCCCUCCCGAGUAACUGGGAUUACAGGCACACACCACCAUGCCCAGCUAAUUUUUUUGUAUUUUUAAUAGAGAUGGGGUUUCAUUAUAUUGGUUAGGUUGGUCUUGAACUCCUGACCUCAAGUGAUCUGCCUGCCUUGGCCUCCCAAAGUGCUGGGAUUAUAGGCAUGAGCCACCGCGUCUGGCAUACAAACUUUUGAUUACAGUUUGACACCUGUUGAUGGACAGAAAAUGGAGUAACCGUCCAGGCAGGAAUGUUCUAGUCUGUGUGACAGUUACAGUUCAUUUUAUAAAUAAACAAUUGACUUUUUUUGGUAGUUAUGGUCCCUACCCUCAGUGCUGUAUCUCUAUUUGGUAUUCAAACAAAUCCAGGGAAUCUGCAAGGCUGAAGGGCAGAUUCUUGGCAAUGGUAAAUUCAGUAGGUCCUGCCACCAUUUGAGGCCUCCUCGGAGACAGCCAUACUAGUCUAAUCUCUUCUUGACUUUCCCUUCUUCUUUCCCAGUCCUCUAAUUCCCAGAGGUCUGUUGUGAAUUCUAAUGCUUUCAGAAAAUAUUACGGAGAAUCCCACAAUGAUAAAAUUUCCCAGUUUUUGUUUUAAAACAAAGUUGAAAAAUAUUAUAUUAGGGGUCAGGGUGAGGUGCUGUUGAUGGUGACAGAUGGCCCCCUUGGCGACAGGGAAGUAUGAAAUAGCAUGGAGUGUGGAAGGGUACUAUGGGUAGCUUAUUUAUUAGAUCAGUAUAAAGUAUAGAUUUAAGAGAGUUAGAUUAAAAUGGCAUGCUUGAUUCAAGUCAUUAAAUUCUAAAGUUCUAUUAAAAUUGUAGAGGAGAUACAAUAAUACAAAUUUCAGCAAUAAGGAUAGAUUUAUAAUCACACUAGGAAGACAAGAAGGGUGCUGUGAAAUAUUUCUAGAAGAUACAAAACAAGGAAUUAGAUCUUGGUGAAACCAAGAGAGCCAAGGAACUGACAGCCACAUGCCGAUGAUAAUUAAAGAAUUACCUCCAGUUGUAGAGACAGCUCUGAGAUGGGGUGUCUGUAGUGUGCUAAGCCAGAUUUUUGAAGGACUAGAUAGUUAUUCUGGUCUCUGACUCAGAGCUGCUGGUCCACAGAAUUCCUCUAAGCUAAAGCUGUAACACAAUUUGAUGUUUGCCAAAUAAGGUGAGACUCACAGAGUAUAUGUGCAGAGCAUAUAAUGCAGAGCAUACAAAUAGGGGCCAUCGAAGUGUGGCAAUGCCCUAGGUAUAUUGUGAUUACCACAAGGAGCUUUAUUCCUCAUACUUAGAAAACAAGCACACAAAGAAAAAUCUGCCAGCUGUCUAUUUCCCAAUUUUCCUUCUGACUGUUCCUUUCUCCUUCCUCACACAAUUAAAAUGCUAGGUUUCCUGUAAUCGCAAUCUUCAGGGAAUUUUUCACUCAAGCCCAGAAAAUAAACUCCAGAUAAUGAUACUGAGAAAUUUAUUGGUUGGAAAACUGCUAUCUACAGGCCUUCCACUACCUAUUUCUUAGUAGAUUUUACAUUUUUAAAGGGUUGUAGAACACCAAAACAAUAUAUGACAGAUACUGUGUUUGGGCCUUAAAGCCUACCCUUUAUAUAAAAAGUUUGUUGACUCCUAGGCUCUCAUUUGCAAGUAGACAAAUGAGAAACAGCAAAUAUUUAAGGAAAAGAGCAACAUGAAAAAUACACAGCAAACUUAACAAGCAGAAAGAAUUCCUGGGGAAACAAUUCAGGGGGAAAAAAUGACCAAGUAUAAUUAGUAUUAUAUGGAAUAAUAAUUACUACUACUUAUAAUAGUUUCAUAUGUAAUCCUCAUCAUAUUAUAUGUCAUAAUCUUCAAAUAUUUUAGAGGUUAUUGUACUAAUUUUAAAAAUGCAAGUUGCUAUAAAGAAGUAUCUUGGAAAUAAACAGUUGUGAAAAUAAACUCUGUUUUAGGCUGAUUAGUUGAAUAAACAUGGCUGAGAAUCAAAUUACUGAGCUAGAAUUUUGAGCUGAAGAUACUUCCAGAGCUUACAAGAAAAGAUAAAAAAGAUGGAAGUUACAGUAAAAGACAUAGAUGUAUCUCUUAAAGACAUAGAAAACCCAGAACACCAUCUGUUUAAAAAUUAAACUUCAUGAGAUUAAGAGCCAUAUGUAUAGAGAAUUCACCAUUGAAUACCCUGCAUAUAUCACAGUGCCAGGUAAAUACUAUGCAAUAAAUAUUUUUGAAUGUAUGUAUGUAUGUUACAGUAUAAAUAUAUAGAGGAGUUCCAGAAAGUGAAAAAAGAAGUGAAGAAUAGGAAAAAAAAAAAAAUCUUCUGAUGAAAGAUUCAUAUUAGAAGUCUCCAGUGCUGAGCAAAAACAAUGAAAAAGUCAUGCAGGAUGAAUACUGACAAAAUAUGUGUAAUCCCAAGCUUAGAAAAAUCUCAAAAUGUCUAAAGAGAAACAGUGUACCUAUAAGGGGAAAAGAAUCACAUUGGUCUCAGACUUGUCAUCUGUUCGUUGGAGUGCUACAACAUACUGCUAUUUUUGAAGUUCUGAGGGAGAACUGUUUUGAAUUUAGACUUCUAUCUUGAGUGAAACUGUCAAGAGUAAGGGCACAGCAAGGACAUUCUACCAAUUUUAGAACAUGCAAGGAUUUCAGAAAUUAACUCAUAAAACACAACCUGCACGGCAUGGUAUCAAAUUAUGUAAAGAAAAACUUGGUAAACAAGAAAUUGUCAAAUUUAUAAUCAUAGCUACGUAUUUGAACACAGCGCUUAGAAAUUGUCAGAUAAAGAGUUCAAAAUAGAGGAAACAUUUUGAAUUAUAUAGUGCACAAAUUUUAAUAGCUAUAGAAUAUUUGUUUUCAAAUGCCAUGAAAAAAUGACCAUGAAGCAAAAACCACAAUAUUUUUUUGUUUGUUGAUAGGUAGGAAUUCAGGGUCCAUCCUGUCAUCACAAUGCAAUGAAACAAAAAAUUAGCAAGUGGAUAGCAAUAAAUCAAUUUUUAAAAAUCAGACAAAAGAAAACACUGUCCUUGUAAUGCUUGCAUUUAAAAGGAAAUAAAAACUUAUGAAAGAGAAUCUUUAUUUUAUUUAAGCAGUUCUAGAUUAUACAAAAUGUUGAAACAUCUCAAUUUGGUCUCUGAGGCUAGCAUAAUCCUUAUUCCAGAAAAUUGUUCAUCAAAGAUAGCUAUAGACCAGUCUCACUUACGAACAAAUGUAAUUUGUUGAAACUGGUCAUGUUGAAAAAACAUGACCAAUUAAAUAUCCCAAAAUAAUGUGUCAUGGUAGAGUAGGGUUUAUCUGAAAACUGCAACAUGACGAUUAUGUAACUCAAUCCUUUAGGAAAUUUAUUACUUUAACUUAAAAAAAAAUACCAUAAGCUUGAUAGAUGCUCGAAAAACAUUUCCUAAGAUUGAACACAUUCCAGAUUUAAAUUUUUCAGGCUGAGAAUAGAAUAAAGCCUUUGUAACUUGGCUAAGGACUAGGAAGGUCUUCCAGAAAGCUUCAUCAAACAUCUGCAUUCAAGUCAGGAUUAAGACAAUAAUGACUGUUGCCUAUGCAACAAUCAUUUAACCCUAAGAAAUAGAAGUAUUAGGAAGAGAAAACAUAGUCCUUAUUUUGAGCAGUGUGAUUGUAGAGACAAACAUCCAAGAGAAACAGUUGAAAAACUAUUAGAAAUGACAAAAGGUAGUUUUGUUUAAUAGUUCACCAUGAAAAUCUGUACUAUAUAGAAAAUCUGUAUAUAGAAUAUAGCAUUGGCCAAUUGGAAAUGUAAUUUGAAAAUCCCAUUUGCAGCAAAACUUGGAACUGUAUACUGUCUAAGAAUAAACAAUGGGAAAAAUGCAAAAUCCUUAUGAGGAAAAUGAUACAUUUUAAUGGAGGAAAUAAAAUGCCUGAAUAAACA